AGCUGGGAACCGCGGGCGCUAGGCGCGCGCACCCAGCACUCGGUCCCAGCCGAUAAAUCUGGGGCAGCGCGCGGUAGGAGCUGCGGGCGGCCAGGCCCCUUCCUGCGUCCGCACCUGGCCCCGCGCGCCCCUCUCGGGCGUCCGGCUUCCGGCGUCCUGGCGGCUCGGGUGGCGGCGGUUCGGGCGGCCGCCUGGCUGCUCCUCGGGGCGGCGACCGGGCUCACGCGCGGGCCCGCCGCGGCCUUCACCGCCGCGCGCUCUGACGCCGGCAUAAGGGCCAUGUGUUCUGAAAUUAUUUUGAGGCAAGAAGUUUUGAAAGAUGGUUUCCACAGAGACCUUUUAAUCAAAGUGAAGUUUGGGGAAAGCAUUGAGGACUUGCACACCUGCCGUCUCUUAAUUAAACAGGACAUUCCUGCAGGACUUUAUGUGGAUCCGUAUGAGUUGGCUUCAUUACGAGAGAGAAACAUAACAGAGGCAGUGAUGGUUUCAGAAAAUUUUGAUAUAGAGGCCCCUAACUAUUUGUCCAAGGAGUCUGAAGUUCUCAUUUAUGCCAGACGAGAUUCACAGUGCAUUGACUGUUUUCAAGCCUUUUUGCCUGUGCACUGCCGCUAUCAUCGGCCGCACAGUGAAGAUGGAGAAGCCUCGAUUGUGGUCAAUAACCCAGAUUUGUUGAUGUUUUGUGACCAAGCUGGCUCCAGAAGAAUGAUCAGAUUCCGGUUUGAUUCCUUUGACAAAACUAUAGAGUUCCCGAUUUUGAAAUGCUGGGCUCACUCAGAAGUGGCAGCCCCUUGUGCUUUGGAGAAUGAGGAUAUCUGCCAAUGGAACAAGAUGAAGUAUAAAUCAGUAUAUAAGAAUGUGAUUCUACAAGUUCCAGUGGGACUGACUGUACAUACCUCUCUAGUAUGUUCUGUGACUCUGCUCAUUACAAUCCUGUGCUCUACAUUGAUCCUUGUAGCAGUUUUCAAAUAUGGCCAUUUUUCCCUAUAAGUUUUAUGUAGUUAAAUGCUUCCUAGAAACCUAAAUAAGAUCUAUUAAUUUCUGACGAGAGGUGUUCUUCUAGAAUUAAUUACUUUUAUCUUUUGUCUUCAUUUGUGGCCAAAAUUAUGUUUACUAGAGGAAAUUUGGGAUCAUUCUCAGCUAAUUCCAAAAUGUAGUGCUCUAUUGCAUGGAUCCUUGGUAAUCCUCAAGCAUCAGAUGCCAUAAGGGGAAACUUAAUUCUGCUAAAUUAAUGUUUAUUUUGUGAGAAGUGACUUUAUCUUCAUUUGGGGUAGAAAAAUUAUUUCUUUAUGUAGUAGAGACAAAUUAUUCUCAUUUUGCAAGUACUUUCAAUUUAAGCUACAAAUUGAGAAAACCGUUAUAAAUAAGAAUAAAAUAGGCCAGGCACAGUGGCUCACACCUGUAAUCCCAGCACUUUGGGAGGCCGAGGUGGGCGGAUCACCAGAGGUCAAGAGUUUGAGACCAGCUUGGUGAAACCCUGUCUCUACUAAAAAUACAAAAGUUAGCUGGGGCUGGUGGUGGGCAUCUGUAGUCCCAGCUAAUUGGAAGGGUGAGGCGGGAGGAUCGCUUGAACCUGGGAGGCGGAGGUUCCAGAGAGCCAAGAUCGCACCACUGCACUACAGCCUGGGCGACAGAACGAGACCCUGUCUCCAAAGGAAAAACAAAAAAGAAGAAUAAAAUAAUUUGGAUGAAAAUCAUGUUUAUUUAAAUAGUAAUGUCAUGAGACUAUUAAAGAUGUGCCAGAGUUUCAAUGAAAAUCAUUAAAGUAGGACAGCUAAGAAAUUAAUAUUAAUAUCAAAAUUAUUGAUAAUCUUAAAUUAUUGAUUAUUCCUUAACGCACUCCAUUCUCCUUUUACAUUUUAUCAUGUUUCUUUUGAAUAUAUGAAUUGGCAAAGGACUUGAUGAAACUGAGUACUAAGAUUUGGUACAGAGUAUGUCAGGAAGACAACUCAGAUUGCCAUUUUAAAUAAAGUUGUACAUGAACAAUAAUUGGAAUCAUCAGGUAAUUUUUUUAAACAAAGGUUCUUCAUUUACUGUUAUGAUUGGAAAAAAAUUAGAAAAUAAAGUAAGUGCCAUAGGCUAAUUAAAAAAUAAAACCUUGGCCGGGCGCGGUGGCUUACGCCUAUAAUCCCAGCACUUUGGGAGGCCGAGACGGGCAGAUCACGAGGUCAGGAGAUUGAGACCAUCCUGGCUAACACGGUGAAACCCCAUCUCUACUAAAAAUACAAAAAAAUGAGCCGGGUAUGGUGGUGCAUACCUGUAGUCCCAGCUACUCGGGAGGCUGAGGCAGGAGAAUGGCAUGAACCCGGAAGGCAGAGCUUGCAGUGAGCCGAGAUCACGCCACUGCACUCCAGCCUGGGCGACAGAGUGAGACUCUGUCUCAAAAAAAAAAAAAAAAAAAAAAAAAAAAAAGUAAAUAAAACCUUAGGGCAAGCAUGUUCCAAAACAGAAGACAUCAAACCAGGGUGUGUUGGCAUUAUUUAUUUUAUGUAGAGUAUUGAGAUGUGAUAAACCUUUGUAUAUGCCAUCACUGCUCCAUUUCCUAAAGUAUUUUGGUGUUUUCAUGGGACUACAUCUUGUAUAAUUUGACAUGUAUGACCUGACUAGUCCUAACAGUUCUUUUUAAACGUGUAUUUGAGACUUAAAUAUUGGAAAAGGUAACCCAGUGCCAUAAAGCAGAAACAGUGACCUUUAAAAUGACUAAAAUUUCAACCCAGUAUAGUUUCAUACCUAUUUCAUGCUUUCUCGUAAGAAAGAAUUUCAUGUUUUAGAAACAUUUCUUUCACUAUGGGAUUAAUAAUAUGACACUGAAAUGGAAUUAUAUAUGUCAGCUACAAUUCAGGCAUUGUUUUGGGAUAUGGUUAGAUUGACAGGCAACGUUUUGGAAUAUGGUUAGACGGGGAGGGAACACGGUACUGUUUAACAUCUUAAGAGUAUGUGGGGGUAUGUGUAUACAGAAUGUUUUUGUUUUUGCUCAUCACAACCAGGUUUCAUCAGUAUUUAAAAUAUUUAAGAUUGUGGCUUGGAAUGUGGUUCAGCCAUUUACUCACUUAUACAAAUAUUCAGAAGUGUAAUAAAAAUGUGAAUGAAGAAAA